GCCUUUUACUUUAUUAUUUAGUAACUAUAUGCUAAGGAUCAUCCCAAGUGAGGGGAUAAUAGGAGCAGGGGUCAAAUGUGUUUAUAGUAGGAUGUAUAGGAUUUAAGUCAGGAGACCAAGAGACUCAGUUUAAUAUUUUUUUCCAAACAGAAACACUAUACCCACAUUCUGUAAAAUAGACACAAAUAUGUAAGAUUAAUUUUAAGAAGGUGCAUGUUCUAUUUUUUCUUUUCUUUUCUAUUUUCUUUUUAUUUAUUUUAAAUAGAGACAGGGUCUCGAUAUGUUGCCCAGGUUGGUCUUGAACUGGGCUCAAGCCAUCCUCCUGCCUUGGCCUCCCAACGUGCUGAGAUCACAGGCAUAAGCCAACACACCUGGCCCACAUUCUAUUUUCUAUAGAAAUGACAUACUUAAAUAAUUUCUCAGAUUGUAGCAAUGCUUCUAUUUACAGAGGACAUUGAUAAUCAACUUUUUCAAAACUGCAAACAUACAGAAAGAUUAAUUUAGGACAUCAAAUAAACUAAGGUUUAAUUAUGAAAAAAAAUCGUAAAAGGCAAAUCAAAGCAACAUCAGAUGUGACCAAAAACGUAUACCAGAUCACUUUCCGGGACUCUUGGAGAAGGGCUUGGGUGAAGAUUUGGGAUGCAGGGGUCUUAUCUGCUCAUUUGAUGAACCAGGAUUCGAAUCACAGGUUCAGUGAGUUGCCUCUUGAUAACCAGUGGUUUGUGGCAGAGCCGGAGCUUGAGCUUAGGAUUCUUGACUCCUACUGCUUUUCUUUUUUCUGUGAUACAUACUAAAGGAUUGGCCGUUAGAUUCUUCUAUGUUUUGUUUUGUCUGGGGAGUAUCUGCAGUGGGAAUAAGUUACCAUUGUGAGGGGUAAAAAGAGGCAGAAAGAGGACCUUUUGUGUUUGUGUUAUUAAGAUUUUCUUUUCCUUAAAUUUCCUUUAGGGUCUGAUAUAGUGAUUUAGGGUGGGGUUGACCCAGAAUGGUUUUUGCCCUAGUUACGAGUAUUGUGGACGUUCUGUUACCUGUUGGGUCGUGCCCAACAAACAUGUUGUUGAGCAGCCUUGGCACUCUGCCUUAGAACACAGCAGUUGGUGGAUAAGUGUGGAUGAGUUGAAGUGAUCGUGGACAGAAGCGUAAACAAAUUUAAUGCAGUCUUGAUAAUUGAACGUAGUCUCCACCCUGAAAUCUGAAUGGAUGCUGUGUAUAAAAUAUCUGCUUUGAAAUACAAUGAAGAGUUUGAUUUCAGUUAAUUUGUUUGGAAUGUCUAUGUUGAAACUUUCUUUUUUUUUUUUUUUUUCCUAUUUUUUCCCCAUUGGGAGUCAGUUAAGAGAGAGGAUUCAGGACAGAAGCUUGCUGUACUUCUGACAGUUUGUGUGGCCCAACUCUAUGCCAUGAGAUUGUCAUUACCCCUGUUACACCUAAGAGCUCUUCUUGGCAGUUGUCCUCUACUUUCUUUACAAAAUAAACUCAAAAAACCAGGUUCCCUGCCUUCCUGUCUCUGGCUUAUCUGCAUGCAGGACUAUCUUUACCUCCUUCUCUUCCAUCUCUCCUACCGACCUUCUGUUUAAGGCCAGUUCCUCUGCAGCCUCUUUUAAAUCAAUCUCUCCUUUUCCCCUUACCAAAGAAUCACCAUUUUUUUUUUUUUGAGUAAGGGUCUUGCUCUGUUGCCUAGGCUGGAGUGCAGUGAUGCGAUCUUGGCUCACUGCAAUCUCCACCUCCCAGGUUCAAGCAACUCUCCUGCCUCAGUCGCCUAAAUAGCUGGGAUUACAGGCGCCUACCACCAUGCCUAGCUAACUUCUGUAUUUUUAGUAGAGAUGGGGUUUCACCAUGUUGGCCAGGCUGAUAUUGAACUCCUGACCUCAGGUCAUCCACCCGCCUCAGCCUCCCAGAGUGCUGGGAUUACAGGUGUGAGCCACUGCACCCAGCCUGAAGAAUCAUCUUUAUUCAGAUAUCUCCUUUCUGUUAGCUCUUCCCUUAGCCUGUGGGUCCCUCUGCUCCUGAAGGUCCCCUCCAGAUGGUCACAGCAUCUUUCCUCCAUUCUGUUAUAACUGAGCUCCUUGGUGAUGAAGAAUGAUCUCUGGCAGUCAUUCAAACCCUUGCCUUGUUUCUUUUAACCCUCUCUGAUAAAUAUUCUGCUUCAUUGAGAUUAUAUGAGCAAGCAACCUCUUAAUUUGCUAUUCUGGAGGAUCUGCCUCAGAGCCUGCCUGACUUGCCUUUUCUGCGGUAGUUUUCAUUAUUGCUUCCGCCUCCAUGGAGGUUUGUCUGUCCUCACUUGUAUGAUGCCACUCUCUCUCUCCUGGCUGCCACCUCUUUGCUUCUUCACGGGCAGCUUUUCCGUGACCUUUUCCAGUGUUCAAGAUUCUGUCCCAGCUGCUUCCUCUUCUCACCAUAUGUUCCCUGGGUUCUGUCUCAUGUGAUAGGUGUGUGCUGCUCUGAUUCAAAUUUCCAGCUCGGAUCUCUUUCCUGAGCACCAGAUUUAACCUCACUUGGGAUCAUGUUGAUACCUCAAAUGCAACUUGUUCAAAACUGUGGUCCCCUAAUCUCUUCCUCUAUUCCUGGUUCAUUAUCUACCUAAGUCAGAAAUGGGAGACCUUGGUGUCAUCUGCUUUCCUCUUUCGAUCCGUCAGUAUAGUGACACCUACAUGUUUGUCUUCCAUCCCGAGUCAACCAAGGUUUCAUUAGUGCUAAUGAUGUUUUUUUUAUUAAUUCUUUUUUUUUUUUGGGACGGAGUUUCGCUCUUGUUGCCCAGGCUGGAGUGCAAUGGCAUGAUCUCGGCUCACUGCAACCUCCACCUCCCAGGUUCAAGCGAUUCUCCUGCCUCAGCCUCUCGAGUAGCUGGGACUACAGACAUGCACCACCGUGCCCGGCUAAUUUUGUGUUUUUAGUAGAGACGGGAUUUCUCCAUGUUGGUCAGGCUGGUCUUGAACUCCCGACCUCAGGUGAUCCGCCCACCUCAACCUCCCAAAGUGCUGGGAUCGCAGGUGUGAGCCACCACACCCGCCUAUUCAUUUUUUUAAAAUUAGGAAAUCUUCUCUUCUGUAGGUCACAUUCUUCCAUUAUACAUACUAAUGCCUUUGGUUUUGAUUCUUCUAAAUGAGGGGAACAUAAGGCCAUAAGCCAAACCAUUUCAAGAUGGAAUAAGAUUUUUUUUUUUAAAUUAUUAUUCCUUUUAUUGAGAUGGAGUUUCACUCUUCUCGUCCAAGCUGGAGUGCAAUGGCGCGUUCUCAGCUCACUGCAACCUCUGCCUCCCGGGUUCAAGCAUUUCUCCUGCCUCAGCCUCCCAAGUAGCUGGGAUUACAGGCAUGUGUCACCACGCCUGACUAAUUUUGUGUUAGUGGAGACGGAGUUUCACCAUGUUGGUCAGGCUGGUUUUGAACUCUUGACCUCACGUGAUCCACCUGUCUCAGCCUCCCUAAGUGCUGGGAUUACAGGCGUGAGCCACCAUGUCCGGGCCGUUUAUAUAUAUAUAAUGCUAAAGGGAGAUAGACAUGAAGACUGAGAAAAAAGCACUUGAAUUUGGUGAUUUAGUGGGGAGGUUUUGUACCAUGAUGAAGACUUCCCAUCAUGCCUGUUCCUCCUUGUGUACCUGUUUCUGAGAUGGCAUCCAGUGGUCCCUUCCAGGUAUUUGAAACUUUGUUGCUAUCAGGAUCCUUCUCCCUUGUUCAUUUUAUUCAGUAAGUUGUGUCAGUGACACCUCCAUAUUCUCUGUGAUAUCCCUUUGUUUUUUUCCUCCCGAAUCUGAAUCUCAAGAUCUAUAAAUGAAUAUUUUCUUGUUGAUUCAGAUCAAACUGAUCAUCAGAUUGUGAUGCAAAUCGCAAAUCUGUUCCUUCUUUUCACCUCUGUUAUCGUUGUCUUAAUUGGAAUAUAGUAGACAGUUUUUAGUUCUCUGGCCUCCUUUAUCAUUCUUCAACAUUUCACACUGUUGAUCACCCUUUUCUUCAUGAAGCUCUCUUCAUUUGACUCUUGGACACCAUUCUCCUGAUUUUCUCACAACAUCUUUGAUGGUUUUUUUCUUGGGCUUCUUUGAGCCUCCCACCUAAAUAUAGGUUACCUCUGCAUUCUGUCCUCUGGCUCAGUCUCUCAUAGAUGAUGUCUGAGCACUCUCAGCCUUAGUUGAGGUUUCUACCACCACCCCCCAUCUGUUGAAUUCCAAAUCUUUGUCCUUAGCAUAGACUCCUGCAGUGAGCCCACAGAUCUGUAUUUUUCAGUUGUUUACCAGAUAACUUCCAUUCAGAGCUUCUGUAGAACUUCAGCUACAAUGGAUUCGAAAGGGGGGACUCAUUCCGCGAACUCUUUCCUGGACUUCCUCCUUUUUUAUUUUCUGUCUUGAUGCAGGGUACUACCAGUUGCUCAUCAUCUAGGUAGGACACCUGAGUGACAUUAAUGCCUCCUUCCUCCCUCUCCACAUUCAUUAGGUCACAAAUCCUAUUGAUUCUACCACUUGAAUUCCUAAAUCUCUCCCAAAUCUGCCUUCCCAUUCUGUCCUCACUGCUUUAGCUUAGACUGUCAUUAUUUCUUGCCUCUUUAGUUUGUUUCCUAACUACUCUCCCAUUGUACAGUUACCUCCCCUGCUUUCUGUCUUUUUUAUUUUUAUUUAAUUAAUUAUUUAUUUAUUUAUUUUUGAGACGGAGUCUCGCUCUGUCGUCCAGGCUGGAGGGCAGUGGCACGAUCUUGGCUCACUGCAAGCGCUGCCUCCCGGGUUCACGCCAUUCUCCUGCCUCAGCCUCCCAAGUCACUAGGACUACAGGCGCCCACCACCACGCCUGGCUAAUUUUUUGUAUUUUUAGUAGAGACGGGGUUUCACCAUGUUAACUAGGAUGGUCUCGAUCUCCUGACCUCGUGAUCCACCCUCCUUGGACUCCCAAAGUGCUGGGAUUACAGGUGUGAGCCACUGCGCCCGGCCCCCUGAUUUCUCUUUACUCCCAUAUAUAAUAUGGCUAAAAUUUGAGUGCUGGUUAUAUCUCAUUUACAAGUGAAAUGUUUGGCAUGCAUUCUCAAAAUCUAUUCAUCACACUGAGUCAUUAUUAUCCAUUUUACUUUGGAGGAGAGUAGUCCCAGGCCUCACAAAUAGGAAGUGGGGCAACAGAGAUCUGAACUCAGGCUGUAUGGUCCAGAGCCCGUGAUCUUAAUUUACCAGUUCAUUUACGGCUCCCUGUGCCAUGUUUGACUGGCCUUUAAAAUCUUUCCUGAGCUGGCCUCUGACUUUACUGUUUCAUCUCCUCCUACUCUGCCUAAUCUGUUUACUGUUUGAUCUCCUCCCAUUCUGUCUAAUAGACCUGGAAUUUCAGGCCUAUUUCUACCUUGUUGGUCUUCCUUGAAGGUGUCAUAUUGUAUCUUUGUUUGUGCAUGUUGCUUCCUCAGCCUUGAAUCCCUGCCUCUUAAUCUUCAAGGCCCAGCUCAAAUGACAUCUCCUGGAAGGGUUUCUUGUCUGUUAGUUAACACCACCGUCCUCUUCUUAAUUAGCCUCUAUUCUUUUCCCAUGAUACACAUAUACACAACUGCCAUAUUUAUAUUUAUAGAAAGUUUGUAAAUAUAUAUAUUCGUAUUUAAAUAAACUUUUAGGAUAGUUUUAGAUUUACAGAAAAGUGGCAAAGGUAGCAUAGAGUUUCCACGAAGCCCAACUCAGUUUCCCUUUUGUUAAUAUCCUAUGUCACUGUAGUGCAUUUGUUAUAACUAAGAAGCUAACAUUGGUACAUUACUAUUGAUUAAAUUUGAUACUUUAUUCAGGUUUCCCCAGUUAGUCUCUUGUGCGUUUUUUCUGUUCCAGGCUCCCAUGGGAUAACACAUUGCAUUUAGUCGUCACAUCAUCUUAGUCUCUUCUGGUCUGUUAUUGUUUCUCAGACUUUUCUUAUCCUUGACCUUGAUAGUUUUGAGAAGUACCAGUCACAUUUUUUUUUUUUUUUUUUUUGGUAGAAUGUCCCUCAGUUUGGGUUUUGUCUGAUGUUUUCCUUAUGAUUAGACUGAGGCCAUGGGUUUUUGGGAGGAAGACCAGAGGUUAAAUGUUCUUUUCAUCACAUAUCAAGUGCACAUGCUAGCAACCUGACUUACCACUGGUGAUGUCAACCUUGCUCAGCUCUCUGAAGUAGUGUUAGUUACUUUGUUAGUAACUAUAAGUUACUUUCUACUCCUCUUUCCAUUCUCCUGUCUUUGGAAGUAAGUCACUAUCACAAGCCACAUUCAAGGUGUAGGGGUGGUAAGCUCUACCUCCUGGAGGGGGGAUUAUUGAUAUAAAUUAUUUGGAAUUCCUCUGUAAGGAAGAUUUGCCUCUUCUCCCUAUUUGUUCAUUCAGUCAUUUAAUUAUAUCAAUUUAUACUUUUUUAUACUUUGGGUUAUAACUCAAUAUUGUUUAUUCUGUUGAUCAGAUUGUUCCAGCUUUGGCUGUUGGGAGUUCUUUUAGAUUGGUUCCUGUGUCCCUUUGACAUGUCCCGUGUCCCAGUGUCCUCGAAAGGGCCAUUUCUCCAAGGAGCCCUAGUUUUAUAUUGGAAAAUGGUAUUAGAAACCAAGAUAUGGGCACUGGAUGUGCACGUUGUUACUGGGGUGUCACUACUUCUUCGCCUUUCAGUGUACAGAUAUAUGGAUGUGAACCCAAGUUUAUAUAAAUAUCUGUAAUUAUUUAUCUGUUCAUCUCUAUGUUAAGAAAAUAGGAGUUUAUACCAACUUCAGCUGAUUCAUUGCCUUCCCUCCUUGCUUAUCUGUAACUUCCCUCUCUGACUAUGAGAAACUUGGCAUCCAUCACCACCAUCCCAUUAGCUACACUGUAAGCGUGGACUUUCUCCCUGUCCCCCUCACUAGGCUGUUAGUAUCUUAGACACUUAUUAAGUCUUUGUUGAUGAGUGAUGAAUCUUGAAGUUGUUAUGUAUCUUACAUAAUAAAAGUUUAGCAUUUUAGCAAAAGCAAUGUAAAUCAAUCUUGUAAAGUUUGAAACAAAACUUUUAACUGCUUUGUUAUGUAACAUGUAUUCAUUGUAGAAAAUAUGAAAAGUGAGAAGGAAAAAAAGCACCUGUUAUUCUAUCACCCAGAGAUAAUACUUAAUAUGUAGACUAUUGUGUCAAAGAAUGCACUGCAGUACCGGGGAAAUUCCCAACAUGAUGCCCAGGAGUUUCUGCUGUGGCUUUUGGACCGAGUUCAUGAAGACCUCAACCAUUCAGUGAAGCAGAGUGGCCAGCCUCCUCUGAAGCCACCAUCAGAGACUGAUAUGAUGCCUGAGGGACCAUCUUUCCCUGUCUGUAGCACUUUUGUACAAGAACUCUUUCAAGCGCAAUACAGAUCUUCUUUGACGUGUCCUCAUUGUCAGAAACAGAGCAACACUUUUGAUCCUUUCCUUUGCAUUUCUUUGCCAAUUCCUCUGCCCCACACAAGGCCUCUCUAUGUCACUGUAGUGUAUCAAGGCAAAUGUUCUCACUGCAUGAGGAUUGGUGUGGCCGUACCUCUGUCUGGGACUGUCGCCAGACUUCGGGAAGCAGUGUCUAUGGAAACAAAGAUCCCCACUGAUCAGAUUGUGUUAACAGAAAUGUACUAUGAUGGGUUCCAUCGUUCCUUUUGUGAUACAGACGACCUGGAAACAGUCCAUGAAAGCGACUGCAUUUUUGCCUUUGAGACUCCCGAAAUAUUUAGGCCUGAAGGAAUUCUCAGUCAAAGAGGAAUUCAUUUAAACAACAACCUAAACCACUUGAAAUUUGGCUUGGAUUAUCAUAGACUGUCUUCUCCUACACAAACAGCAGCAAAGCAGGGGAAAAUGGAUUCUCCCACAUCAAGAGCAGGCAGCGACAAGAUUGUCCUGUUGGUGUGUAACCGAGCCUGCACUGGGCAACAAGGGAAAAGAUUUGGACUGCCUUUUGUGCUGCACUUAGAGAAGACAAUAGCUUGGGACCUUCUGCAGAAGGAAAUCUUGGAGAAGAUGAAGUAUUUCUUGAGGCCCACGGUUUGCAUUCAGGUGUGUCCAUUCAGCUUGCGUGUGGUCAGUGUUGUUGGAAUAACAUAUUUGCUGCCCCAGGAGGAGCAGCCCUUGUGCCACCCAAUAGUAGAAAGGGCAUUAAAAUCUUGUGGACCAGGUGGCACUGCUCAUGUGAAAUUAGUAGUCGAGUGGGACAAGGAGACAAGAGAUUUCUUAUUUGUAAAUACUGAGGAUGAGUAUAUUCCUGAUGCAGAAAGUGUUCGUCUGCAAAGGGAGCGUCAUCAUCAGCCUCAAACCUGCACUUUAUCCCAGUGUUUCCAACUGUACACCAAAGAGGAGCGGCUUGCCCCCGAUGAUGCCUGGCGUUGCCCACACUGUAAGCAGCUGCAGCAGGGAAGCAUUACGUUAAGCCUCUGGACUCUGCCUGAUGUGCUUAUUAUACAUCUAAAGAGAUUUCGGCAGGAAGGAGACAGGCGCAUGAAACUUCAGAACAUGGUCAAAUUCCCCUUGACUGGCCUGGACAUGACACCUCACGUGGUUAAGAGGAGCCAGAGCAGCUGGAGUUUGCCAUCGCAUUGGUCCCCGUGGAGACGGCCCUAUGGACUCGGGAGGGACCCUGAGGACUACAUCUAUGACCUGUAUGCUGUGUGCAAUCACCAUGGCACCAUGCAAGGGGGGCACUACACAGCGUACUGUAAGAACUCUGUGGACGGCCUCUGGUACUGCUUCGAUGACAGCGAUGUGCAGCAGCUGUCAGAAGAUGAGGUCUGCACGCAGACAGCAUACAUCCUCUUCUACCAGAGGCGGACAGCCAUCCCGUCAUGGUCAGCCAACAGCUCGGUGGCAGGCUCCACAAGUUCUUCCCUGUGUGAACACUGGGUGAGCCGGCUCCCGGGCAGCAAGCCAGCCAGCGUGACCUCUGCAGCUUCCUCCAGACGCACCUCCCUGGCGUCGCUCUCUGAGUCCGUGGAGAUGACUGGAGAAAGGAGUGAAGAUGAUGGAGGCUUUUCAACUCGACCAUUUGUGAGAAGUGUCCAGCGUCAGAGUUUGUCAUCCAGAUCUUCUGUCACCAGCCCCUUGGCCGUCAAUGAAAAUUGCAUGAGACCUUCAUGGUCCCUGUCUGCUAAGCUGCAGAUGCGCUCCAAUUCUCCAUCCCGAUUUUCAGGGGAUUCGCCAAUUCACAGCUCUGCUUCCACCUUGGAGAAGAUUGGGGAGGCAGCAGAUGACAAGGUCUCCAUCUCUUGCUUUGGUAGCUUGCGGAACCUUUCUAGCAGUUACCAGGAACCAAGCGACAGUCAUAGUCGCCGUGAGCACAAGGCUGUGGGCCGGGCCCCUCUGGCUGUCAUGGAAGGCGUGUUCAAAGACGAAUCGGACACCCGCAGAUUGAACUCCAGUGUCGUAGAUACACAGAGCAAACAUUCAGCACAAGGGGACCGCCUGCCCCCGCUCUCUGGUCCAUUUGAUAACAAUAAUCAGAUCGCUUAUGUGGAUCAGAGCGACUCCGUAGACAGCUCUCCAGUCAAAGAGGUGAAAGCCCCCAGCCACCCAGGCUCACUCGCAAAGAAACCAGAGAGCACAACUAAGAGAUCCCCCAGUUCCAAAGGCACUUCUGAGCCAGAGAAAAGCUUGCGGAAGGGGAGACCAGCCUUGGCAAGCCAGGAGUCAUCCCUUUCAAGUACAUCCCCUUCUUCUCCUCUUCCUGUAAAAGUCUCUCUAAAGCCCUCCCGCUCCCGCAGCAAAGCAGAUUCUUCUUCCAGGGGCAGUGGACGGCAUUCAUCCCCUGCCCCUGCCCAACCCAAAAAGGAGUCAUCCCCGAAAUCUCAGGACUCCGUGUCAUCUCCUUCGCCACAGAAGCAGAAGUCAGCCUCGGCCCUCACCUACACUGCUUCCUCCACAUCUGCCAAAAAGGCCUCGGGCCCUGCCACAAGGAGCCCUUUCCCACCUGGGAAGAGCAGGACUUCAGACCACAGCUUGAGUAGAGAGGGCUCCAGACAAAGCUUGGGUUCUGACAGAGCCAGCGCCACCUCCACCUCCAAACCCAAUUCCCCUCGGGUGAGCCAGGCCCGAGCAGGGGAGGGCAGGGGGGCCGGGAAGCACGUGCGGAGCUCCUCCAUGGCCAGCCUGCGCUCCCCCAGCACAAGCAUCAAGUCUGGUUUGAAGAGGGACAGCAAGUCUGAGGACAAGGGGCUGUCCUUCUUCAAAUCAGCCUUGAGACAGAAGGAAACCCGGCGCUCGACGGAUCUUGGCAAGACAGCCUUGCUCUCUAAAAAGGCUGGUGGGAGCUCUGUUAAGUCUGUCUGUAAGAACACCGGGGACGACGAGGCAGAGAGAGGCCACCAGCCUCCAGCUUCCCAGCAGCCAAAUGCAAAUACAACGGGAAAAGAGCAGCUUGUCACCAAGGACCCUGCUUCUGCCAAACAUUCCCUGCUGUCCGCUCGCAAAUCCAAGUCUUCCCAACUAGACUCUGGAGUUCCCUCGUCUCCGGGUGGCAGGCAGUCUGCAGAGAAAUCCUCAAAAAAGUUAUCUUCUAGCAUGCAAACCUCUGCACGGCCUUCUCAAAAACCUCAGUGAUAUUUCUGCAAUCAAAGUGUUUUAUCUGUAAAGAUGUUUAUUUAUUUAGAACCCCUGCCCUCCCACCAAAGCCUCCUGUGCUUUUGUUUUGUACUUUUUUGAGUCACGUGCCCGACUGUGUGUGUGUGUGUGAGUGUAUGCGUGUGUGUGUCUAAUUCAAUUGCAAAUUGUUCAAAGCGUCGCCUUAUUCUGCCAUUGAACCAAAUAACAGCCAUAGGCAAAACAUUGACACCAAGCUAACUGGAAUAAUUGUAGACGAUACCCAGGACGGUCCCUUUAGCAAUUGUACAUAUUUCUUUCUAGAGAACUCUAAUGACUUUCUUUGGAUAUGAGGGUUUUGAAACCUGUGAACCAGAAAAGCUACCAUUAGUGCGUAGAAGGAGGAAGGAGCUGACUCGUGUUUCUUCUGAGCAGGACUUGUCCUUACUGUGGAUUGUGGGUGGCACCAGGAGCUCUAAAAACUGUGACUCUAACAACGAAACAAAUCGAGGGAAAAACUCUUGCUUUCUGCACUUUCGCCCCAUCUACCAGUCUUUGUAAAGGGCAAUAUUUUAACACUAAUGUUUCUCAGGUAUAUACUCAGCUAGUCUAGGAUGGUUGCACACCAGUAAAUGGAUUAAAGAGGAAGGUGCCAUGUGGGUGACUGUGUCAUUUCUCCUACUGCCACAGAUAGACAUUUUCGAGGUAGAAAUGAAGCCUUUCACCACCUUCCUAUCUGUGGUGACAUGUGCACCAAAACCUGUCUUGACUCUUGGGAUAGGUCCUAGGAAGUGGCAGAUUGGAUAGCCAGAAAGCCAGUCACUCGUUUAAUUUUUUUUCCUUCUGAAAUUACUAGCUAAGGCUCUUGGAAUUUUGCACUGUAGUAGAGCAGUUAACACCUUUGACAGAUUCCUGGAAAAAACUUCUAGAUUCUAAACUGGGUGAAAGACUGGACAUCAUUUUCCUUGUCAGGUGUUGCAUUUUUCCGUUAGAGGUGGGAAGCUCCACGAUGCCCUGUGUCUGUGGGCUCAUGUUCCCUCAUCUUGUAGCUUGGAGAGGAAAGAAGUUGCCUUCUGCCAAAAGCCAAUGGUGGUAUGUUGAAGCGUUGUGUGAUCAAGUGUUACAUAUGCACUUCAGAUCCUGUCUGUCAGUCUCUGUUAGGGCUGCCUUUCAGUAACUCAUUUAUUAUUUCUUCUUUGUUCUUAAGAUUUCAUCUCAUGCCCAGAACUCACAAGCAGGUUUUGGAGUGUGUUCCAUCUGGCCGUGUCAGUGCAAAUUGCAUUUCUUACAAAGGAGAACCUCACCAAAAAAAACCUCACAGAUAAGCAAAGUAUAUAGUUUUGCAAGCUUUUUCAAGGUCUCCUGGCAAUACUUUCCUGCUCAAUUUUUAGCUUUUCUUUUUUUUUUAAAUGUCAAGAGAGUGAAGGUCUUGAUUCUCUCUGAAUAGCAUUUGUCACUUUGCCAGUAAAUACAGCAUGCUAAGUUUAUGUGCUUUUAAAUAUUAGCGUUUUUCGUCAGACUCUUCAAGUUCUUCUUGAACCCUUGGUGCACAGAUCCAUAUAUAACCUCCCUUUUCAGUAUUGCUGUGUGUGAAUUAACUACAACACAUAUGCAUGCAUAGCUGUGAAUUCUGCACUACUUUUUUUUUCUUUUUUCCCCCCAAGAAUAUCUCUUGGGAAAAGUUUUUAGUACGUUACUUAACUUUAUUUUGCUGCUAAUUUGCGCAUUAGCCGGUAACUUGCAAGUCUGGAGACCACUUACUGUUGAGGGUAGCUGGAAUUUUAGACCCUUGGCAGUAUUUAAGAUUUAGACAUUUAGCCUUGUGAAAGUUACCACAGUGCUCCAUGUGAUUCAUUGACUGUGAGCCUGUUGUCCAUUGCACUCAGCCCUGUACUCACUUCUUCACUCGCUGUCCUGGUUUUACUGUUCAGAUUUUGGUGGGUUCUCAAAGCAGUACCACUCUCAUCUGCUCAGUACAUCUGCGGCAACUGGCUGCCUUCGAUGCUGUCAUUGCGUUCAGCCCAGCACAUCACAGCCCCAUCAGUGUGUAGCCACCGCUCUCGUUUUUCUGUAUCGCUUUUAUCUCCUGAAAAAGAUGCACCAAAUAAGAGAUCAUCUAUAUCAGGAAUUGAAUGUCUAACUCAAACCUCUCAUUUUUGUUUAAUAGGUAGAUCUCAUUUGAAGUCUCCUAUCUGAAUCUCUGAAACAAUUAUAGUUUGAUUAGACAAAGGUUUUUAAUAACACUUCUUUUUUGCUGUAGUCAAGCAUUAAUAGAAACUAGUUUAAUUUUCACAGUGGUAAAUAUUUUUAUUCUUGAGUUAUCUAGGAAUGGAUUUUCCACGAUGUCUAGUGACUUAAAAAAAAAAAGGAAAAACGUUUCUACAAAUCCCUUUGGUUUUCCAUGGGAUCUGGAAUAAAAUGUCAGUGUCUAUAAACUGUAUGUCAUGGAGUUUAGUCCUUGUUUCAGGUUUAAUAGAAAAAAUCAGGAAGUAUCAUGGCAUUGUCUAGACAUCAUGAAGCUAUUUUAUUUCCAUAGUUGGUAAACAGUGAAAAUUUCAUUAUCUCCAACUACUAGGUACAACUUUAGGCCACAGGAAAGGUUAUUUGGCCCGAAAGUUUGGAGGUGCUCCUUGAGGUGGGAAGUAUCUUGUGGGAAAGUAGUUACUUGAUUCAAUUUAGUUCAUUGGUAGGGUUGGGGACUUGGUGUUGGUUUCUUUCUUUCUUUUCUUUUUUUUUUUUUUUUUAAUUUUCCCAGCAAUAUUUAGCACAAUGAGCGUGUAUGUGCUUUGGGGUUAAAAAUUAUCUGCUAGGGAUGAUAGGCCUGGGUUUCUCGUUGACAUCUAGAUGGGCCUGAUUAGAGCAGUCAUCUCCUGGUAGGCACAAAAUAAUCACCAACAGUAAUGUUGUAUCUGUAAUGUUUGUUUGCUUUUUAAAGUUUUAUUCUUGAUUUCUUGUAAACAUCCAUUGCACUGAGGCCGUAUCAUUCCUUAAGACAGCCCUACAUCUUGCCUUGGUAAUCCCUUAGAUAAUGUGGAAACUCAAACCGUUAGGCUCCAGUCAUCUUAGACCAUUUCCCAUCCGUUUUGUAUUUUCUCGUCCUGAAAGCAGCUGAACUGAAAGUAAGUAAUAAUAUGCUGGACCAGUGGGAACGGAUGUGGGAGUAUUUGUGGUGUGCUAAAAUACUGUAAUUAUCUGUGAGGCUGCCUGACACGCUUUUGCAAUCUUGUUUUCAUCAUUCAUUCUGCAAACGUUUAUGGAGGGCCUUCUUUGAGCACAGAGGCAAAACUGAAAGCUUCAGGGAUUUGCUGUAGCUGAGGAGCCCUGGGAGCACAGCCCAUCAAGCAAGGGAUGUGAUGGUGUCCUAAAUGGAGUGACAGUUCUCCUGGGAAAAGAGAUCACGUGGAUUCCGGUCAAAUCGGCUAAGGCUUGUGGUUCUCUUGAGCAAGUCUGUUCCUUCUGGAAACCAAAAGUGCCCUUCAUCUUUAGAGACAUUUUACUCUUCCAUCCACCUUUUCAGACUGAGCUGUCUCUACUAUUUAGGGGUUGAAAAUCCAUUACACAGUCACUUUACGUUAACAUUGGGUCAUCUUAUGUUUGUAUGAGACGGAUGUGGGAUUUGAGGGGAACAUUGUCAUUCCCUUAAAAUAACUAUCAUGAAAAAAAUAGCAACAGUAUGUAAAGGGACCAAGAGUGGCAGCCUUUAGGGAAAAUGGAGCAGAGAAGAGCUGUGAACAAAGCUCAUUUAUUUGAAAUAAGCGUGCUUUAUUUCACAUAGAGGGGCAUCAGACGUUACAUUUCAUUCGGACAAAUUACUGAACAGCCGAAGUGAUUGUUUCCAAUGUAGGUUAUUAUAAUUAUUGGAUACAAAGAUUUAACUAGUGUUUCUGGGUUGGAUUUUUGAAAUAGUAUGCAAGUCAUAAGCACAGUUUCAAUAAAACACGUAUUCUGGAGGUGCGUGGAACUUUGUAUUAUUUGUAGUUGAGAAAGGCAAACUUUGCUGACAAACCAGUACCUAUCACAAACGAACACAAAAAGUAGCUGUUACUGUGCAGGCUGUCUUUAACUUUCAUUUCAUAAAGGGUACAUUAUUGUUAAACUCUACUACAUGGUUUGGGGAGAAAUCCAGUGGUUUUAUUUAAAUGAACACUCUCACACUGCCUUUUGAUCAACUUUCAAAGUAUUUUGCAGAUGCAUUUUGAGCAUGACCAUUUUUUUCCCCAAGUAAAAACAAUUGUGCGUGGCCUCCAUAUAACUCAGAAAGCAUGCUCUUACUACCUAUGCAAGCAAACAAUAAAACAUAUAGACAUGAAAUGUUAAGUCUUAAAAAAAAAAGGCAACAAUUAUGGAGCUCUAUUUUUAAAUUUGUGAUUUUCAAAAUAUGGCUUACUCAUCAUUGUGUAGAAGAGCAUGAAUGCGAUUUCUUGUUUUGCUCUGCAUAUAUUUCUCUGCUGUUUUUCUGAUCAUUGGCGAGAUUGUAAAGUAUUUUGCAAGCAGAAGUGGAAUUGGAUAUGUUGAACACACAUCAUUGGUGUACAUACUGUAUUUAGCCUGAAGACUUUCCUAAAGUGUUUUGUUCUAAAAAUAACCUGCCAUUUUCUAUAGAUUUUAAUUUUUUAUAUCUUCAAGGGUUCUAUUUUGGUCACAAGGAAAGAAUGUGGCUUCUAAUAGUGCUAAGAAUUAAAAGAUGCUUUUAUAGAGACUUAGAGCUAUUUUGAAAAGCUUUGGGGCUUCCCAGCCACUGAUCACAAUUAGACUAAGCCCAUGGAAUUUCUGGGAGUGUUGUGCAGUGGAUUCGGUUCUAGAUCCAUCUUACAUUUGUUUAGUGUUUCCCAAUUUUUGGGAGAAGGGGUGCACAGCAAAUUUGAGAGACUUUUUUGAAUCUCACACAUGUAUUUUCCUCAAGAUUCUUUUAAGCCUCUUCUGAAUGACUUGUCUGAGAUAGUGAAGACCCACAUUAACUAGAAUCAGCUGGGGAACUUUAAAAAAUACAGUGCCUGGGUCCCAGUCCCUAGCUUUUGAUCUAAUUCAUGUAGGGGUGGGAUCCAGGAAUUACCAUGUAUUUUAAAAGCUUCUGGGUGUUUCUAAUUUGCAGACAGAUUGAGAACCACUAUGAUACGUCAUCCCUUUACUGAGAAUUAUGGCGAGAAUCACUGCCAUUUGAAUUACUCAGGAGUGACUGAUUCCUCAGUUGUGUAGGAGAAGCAGAAAAAAUAAGAAUAAAAAGAAUUGAGAGAUACUGAUAUCAAACUCCCAUUUGAAAUACAAGGGCCCUUCUGAUUCAAGGCCCAGUUGGGGAGCUUGGACCAUGUUGUGAAUGGCCUAGCACUCGCCAGUCUGGUGGAAAUUGGUGGUCUUAGUUGCUGGAGCAGGCUGAGUGUCCCCGCGGGGUUUGCAUCUGUCCCCAGAACCUUUUCCCCAGGCCCGUGGGGGAAUAGGGAAGUCACUCUGAGCUAGAAAUUGUCGAAGAAGAAAAGAAACAACCUUCCUAGCCUUGGAAAGCCUGUCCCUGCUUUUGAUAGAAUUAUUGCCUUUUUGUAGGAAUUACAGUAGCAAACCCCAGGCUGCCGCUGAAUUUCCUACUUUUGCUCAUUCUCUAGGAUAGUUCUUAUCCAGAAUGUGGUUUCAGGAAUUCUUUUUUUUAGUUUGAAAAUGAAUGUGAAACAUUUUCUUUGGUGUCUUUUUUUUAAAAAAAAAAAACCCUUAUUGCUAUUUUUUCGUGUUUUUGUUUUGUUUUGUUUUUUGUUUGUUUUACCAUUAAGUAAUACACAUCCCAGAAUUUGGCACUCUGUGUUAACUGUGGAGGCAAAUAAAAUUUAGUUUUAAUCUGUGGUGAGCUGAAUGCACUACAACACCUUCGAAGUAAUCUGAUGGUUUCAUUCUGUCGAGCCUCAUGCUGCCUACAAAACACCACAAUUUACCUGGUGUUUUCAACAUUUUAAGGAAUGAAGAUACAAGUAGACAUGCAAGUUGGAAAUGUUUCUUUAGAAAGGCCAUCCAGAAUAAUGAUAUCUGUUGCAGUCGUCCAAAUGCAAUAUGAAAUUUCCUAGGUGCUAUUAUAAACGGUGUGGUGUCAUACCAAAUGCAAAAGCAGUUACAGUAUUUCCGAAGUUGGAGUUCUCUUUGUAGGCCUUUCAAAUACGUGUUUGCAUUCCAUAGAGGUCUGCUCACCAACUGUGCCUCUCACCACUGGUUAAAAUUGAAUUUAAGCCUCAUUGACAUAAGUCGUUUCUUGAUUGAACUCUUCAGUUUUUACACUGGAAUUUCUGUAGUUGUCUUGAAAGCUGCAUGUCACAUCACUGUACACAAAGUGCUUUGGUAUUACUCAUGCACCGUGGAUAGUGAUUUCUGUGUCGUUUUCAUUUUCAGUUGUACAGUAAUAUGGAAGGCAGGAUGUCUUUCCUAGAGGCUGGAAGAAAAGUGUAUCGUACAUUUUAAAUUUAUUUUAGAACAAGUGCAUGAGAUGUGUCACUGAUUUCUGUUAUUUAUUUGUAUGUUUUAUUAUUCAAAGUGUAUGCACUUUUAAGAAGCAGAAUUUAUAUUUUUACGUUUGAAACGUUUUAUUUCUGAAACAGCGUUGAUUAUAUAGUAUACAGUUGGAAUUAAGAGAAAAGUGGAAAAUGUAACAAAAUACAAUAAAUUUAUUACAAGAUGUCCUCUUCAA